GGAGGUAAGAACUAAGACGUUCUUAAACCCUACUACGUGCUGGAAUCCUGAAGUGCCUGCCAUCAUUCAAACUUAAGCACUAACUCUCUAGAGAGACACUGCCAUUCAUACCACAGAACGAGAAGGCAGUGGCGAUCCUCAACGGCUACAUGUCACUGCCUGCCACUUCCGGCUCCUGCGUCGCUCCGGAAGCCUGCGAGUUCCGGAAGCCUUGGUAAUCCAGAUUCGGCUAGGAAAAGACAAGCUUUCCAGAGAAUGUUUCAGAGAAAGUUACGUGGAGCGUGGGCGUUUCGCAGACUCCUAAGUGGUCUGGAACCUAACCUGCAGUGUCUCUGAGCUUCUGGCAAGUAUGAGGCAAGGAUUUCACAGAAGAACUUGGAGCAAAAAUUCCCACUGUCAUAGCUAUAGGCUGUCCAGUCUUGAGGGAGCUGCAGGAACAGGAAAAAGAGACCUUCAGAGAAGACAUGGCUUCCAGAAAAGAGAAUGCGAAGAGUGCAAACAGAGUGCUAAGAAUAAGCCAGUUGGAUGCACUUGAACUAAACAAGGCCCUGGAGCAGCUAGUUUGGUCCCAGUUUACUCAGUGCUUUCAUGGAUUUAAACCUGGGCUGUUAGCUCGCUUUGAGCCAGAGGUGAAAGCGUGCUUAUGGGUUUUCUUGUGGAGAUUCACCAUCUACUCCAAAAAUGCCACAGUGGGACAGUCAGUUUUGAAUAUUAAGUACAAAAAUGAUUUUUCCCCUAACCUGAGAUAUCAGCCACCCAGUAAAAAUCAAAAAAUCUGGUAUGCUGUUUGUACAAUUGGUGGCAGGUGGUUAGAAGAACGAUGCUAUGAUUUGUUUCGAAACCAUCAUUUAGCAUCAUUUGGGAAAGUCAAGCAGUGUGUGAAUUUUGUGAUUGGACUUUUGAAAUUAGGUGGGCUGAUUAAUUUUUUGAUUUUCCUUCAGAGGGGAAAGUUUGCAACUUUGACAGAACGUCUCCUAGGUAUUCAUUCUGUAUUUUGCAAGCCUCAAAACAUAUGUGAAGUUGGCUUUGAAUACAUGAAUAGGGAACUUCUCUGGCAUGGUUUUGCUGAAUUUCUGAUUUUUCUCUUACCACUUAUCAAUGUCCAGAAGUUGAAAGCCAAGCUGUCUUCAUGGUGUAUUCCUCUUACUGGUGCACCUAAUAGUGACAAUACAUUAGCCACCAGUGGCAAAGAAUGCGCUCUAUGUGGAGAGUGGCCCACCAUGCCUCACACCAUAGGAUGUGAGCAUAUUUUCUGUUAUUUCUGUGCUAAGAGUAGUUUCUUAUUUGACGUGUACUUUACUUGUCCUAAGUGUGGCACAGAAGUACACAGUCUGCAGCCACUGAAAUCAGGAAUCGAGAUGUCAGAAGUAAAUGCUCUUUAGAAACUAAAAUUGCUUCCUUUGAGGAAAAAAAUGCACCGUGUUUAAAUUCUUAAUAUUAGUCAUCCUAAGUAUACCAUUUAUGUAUCCUUUAUAAGGAAUGUGCUCCUAGCCACUGUCUUCUCCUUUCCAGGCAUGACUGAAAUCUAAUCACUGGAAACCAUGUGAUUCUAAAUAUAUUAUGUAAAUGUUAAUGUAUUAUGUUUUUUAAAUCAUUGCAUUCAAUUUUUAAUGUCAAGAAUAAUGGACAGCUUUUGUCAGGUGACUACUAACAAUGCUCCUUCAUUUUACUACUUCUUAAAACAAGGUUGGAUUCUAAAGAUAAAGAUUUUGGAGACUCUGGGAUGAGUGUGCAUUUAUUUUCAGAGUUGACAUAAUAUGAUAAUGUGACAAUUAUGAGACUGUUUUAAACCUUAAGACCUGAUGCCUCAGUUGUAACUUUUUUUUUUUUUUCUGAGACGGUGUCCUGCUCUGUCACCCAGGCUGGAGUGCAGUGGCGCGAUCUCUGCUCACUGCAACGUCCGCCUCCCGGGUUCAAGCAAUUCUCCUGCCUCAGCCUCCCGAGUAGCUGGCACUGCAGGUGCAUGCCACCAUGCCCGGGUAAUUUUUGUAUUUUUAGUAGAGAUGGGGUUCACUGUGUUAGCCAGGAUGGUCUCUAUCUCCUGAUCUGGUGAUCCACCUGCGUCAGCCUCCCAAAGUGCUGAGAUUACAGACGUGAGCCACUGUGCUUGGCCGCCUCAGUUGUAAUGUUAUGCUUUUCUCUGAAGCCAAUUUUUAAGAAGUUCAGUCCUCAGCUGUCUGACCCCUCCACAGUUGGCUUUAUAUUCAGAAAGUAAAAAUUACUUAAGGCAGCUUGGAAGUGAGGCCUGGGAACUACUGGGGGCAACUAGUAUGAACAGCACUAUUUACAGGUCUCUUUCUCUUGCCUUUGAUUCAGAGCUGUCAUUCUCAGUAAAUAUUGAUAGUUUUAUUGAAACAAAAGGGGUCUUUAGCAUGGGAAUAGUAACAGCAGUGCAUAAUCAAGAUAAUUCUGUAUCCUUCACUCUUUUUCUCUGCCUUUUUUUACUUAAAAGUAAAUUCAGACUCUUAAAAUGGUAUAGAAUUAUUAGCUUGAACAUUGAAUUAUCUCGUCUUAACUAGAAUGUUUUUUAAAAAACAGUUUUUAAAUGUUUUUAAAUAAACAUCUUGCUAGUAUGAUGGAAAUACACUGCCAGUUCAUUUUUCUCUUCACCUUUCAUUGAACAAGUACUCAGGUGCCAGGUACUGAUGUAGCCAUUAGAGGCACAACAGUAUAUUAAGCAGGAAAAAUCAAGUUACCUUCAUGGAGUUUACAUUCUGUGAUUGAAUGAACUGUAAGUUUAAUUUAGGUUCAAUUUAGUGUAAGAUACUGAAGAAGUUUUGUAGUUUGAGUUAAGAGUAUUUUACAUCUUAAGAAUUUGCCUUCUUUUGCCUUCUGUAAUUUUAAAACAUUAUUGUAGAAAACACCAACAAUUCAGGAAAAAAUAUAAAAUCAACUUUCCCACAAUUUUUUGAGAGAGAUCAUCACUAUAUUUUACUAUAUUUGUAGAUUUGUUGCACGUACAUUUCUUAUUUACAAAAUUAUUAUAAUGCAUAAAAAAUAGCAUUUUUUCCUAUGUAUAAAUAUUCUUCAAAACUAUUUUAGGGCUGAGCACAAUGGCUCAUGCCUGUAAUCCCAGGCUCCCUACUUAGGGAGGCUGAGCCCAGGAGUUUGAGUUCGUUUCUAAAAAAAUAAAAAUAUAUACAAACGUCUUUGUUUUUUGUUUGUUUGUUUGUUUUUGGUGAGAAAGGGCCUCACCCAGUCACCCAGGUUGGAGUGCAGUGGUGUGAUCAUGGCUAACCGCAGCCUUUCCCUCCCAGGGCUCAAGCGAUCCUCCCAUCUGAGCCUCCCAAGUUGCUGGGACCACAGGCCCAUACCACCAUGCCUGGCUAAUUUUUGUAGAGAUGAGGUCUCACUUUGUUGCCCAGGCUGGUCUUGAACUUCUGGGCUCAAGCAGUCCUCCUACCCUGGCCUCCCAAAGUUGUGGGAUUACAGGCAUGAGCCACUGCACCCAGCCAUAAUAUAUUUUUAAAAUGCUAUGUAUAUGCCAUCAUAUUCCUAUUCCUAUUAUUAUUUAACCACCAUCAUAGAGCAUUUAGGUUCUUUUCACUUUCUGUUGUGAAUAAUGCAAUGUUGAAUCUGAGUUCAUUAAGUGAAGAGUCCAGCUGCACACUGCAGGCCCAGUCUGGAUGUAGGUGCUCAGAUGGUUCUCUUUGAGACAGGCUUUAUCCUUUGGCUCUCAUUUUUUUGAUGAGUGUACAUGGCAUGAGGGACACAGAUUCCGCUAGAAUUCAAAUCCCACUUGUGUAUAACCUAGGGCAAUGUGCCACAUCUCUGCACAUCUGUUCAUUGUAAGGAUUACAUGUUUAGUGUAUAUAAAGCUCUUAAAACAAUGCCUGACACAUAGUAAAUAGAAUAUAAUAGUAGUGCUUUCCUUUGCUGUUGUCAGUAUUACUCUGAGUCGGUUUCAUUCUCACACAGAAUGAUGGCCGCUAGAAGCUCAAGGCUUAUAAUCUGCUAGCUUUCUGAUCCCACUGGCAUGAGAUACUCUUGCCUAAUAGUUACAGCUAAAGUCCAGGAGCUCACUGUUACUGGUCUGCCUUGGAUUAUGUGCACAUUCCUGAACCAGCCACUAUAGCUAGGGGAUGGAAAAUACUGUUCCUGGUUACUUAAAUGUAGGUGAUGCUCCUCCCAUAUACCACAUGAACCUAAAGGAGUCCUGGAGGAGGCCGUUCACCACAGGAAACUGAGGUGUUCUUAGAAGGGUGGAUGCUGGCAGAUCUCUACUAGUUAGAGUCUACAUUUGCCUUACUCAUUUCAAAAGUCCACAUUGCAGUCUCAUUUUACCAGUGAUCUAGCUUGAUAAGGACAUUCAUAAGUAACUGGAUGAUUCUUUAACAUUGCAGAUUUGAAAGGAUUAAAUAAAGUCAACAAAAUUGUUAUAUCAA